ACCCUUCUCUGUCUACCUCUGGGCGGGACUGCCGGGUGAUGAGAUACUCGGUCGGCGACGGUAGAACGGGCGACGGCGACAACCGCAAUCACAUCCACGACGGUGAUCAUGGCAGAGAAUCACGCCCAGAAUAAAGCCAAGCUCAUCUCUGAGACCCGGAGGAGGUUCGAAGCUGAGUAUGUGACAGAUAAGUCAGAUAAAUAUGAUGCACGUGAUGUUGAAAGGCUACAACAAGAUGAUAACUGGGUUGAAAGUUACUUAUCUUGGAGACAUAAUAUUGUAGAUGAAACACUGAAGAUGCUCGAUGAGAGUUUUCAGUGGAGGAAAGAAAUUUCUGUCAAUGACCUUAAUGAAUCCUCCAUUCCCAGAUGGUUAUUGGAAAUUGGUGUUAUUUAUCUCCAUGGUUAUGACAAAGAAGGUAACAAAUUGUUCUGGAUCAGGGUGAAGUAUCAUGUAAAAGACCAGAAAACCAUAUUGGACAAAAAGAAGCUCAUAGCAUUCUGGUUGGAACGUUAUGCUAAGAGGGAAAAUGGGAAACCUGUAACAGUGAUGUUUGACCUGUCAGAAACUGGAAUAAAUAGCAUUGACAUGGACUUUGUACGCUUUAUCAUCAACUGCUUUAAGGUUUAUUACCCUAAAUACCUCUCAAAAAUAGUGAUCUUUGAUAUGCCUUGGUUAAUGAAUGCUGCUUUCAAAAUUGUGAAAACCUGGCUUGGUCCAGAAGCAGUGAGCUUGUUGAAGUUUACAAGCAAAAAUGAAGUCCAGGACUAUGUCAGUGUAGAAUACCUGCCUCCCCACAUGGGUGGAACUGAUCCUUUCAAGUAUAGCUAUCCACCACUAGUAGAUGAUGACUUCCAGACCCCACUGUGUGAGAAUGGGCCUAUUACCAGUGAGGAUGAAACUUCAAGUAAAGAAGACAUAGAAAGUGAUGGCAAAGAAACAUUGGAAACAAUUUCUAAUGAAGAACAAACACCUCUUCUUAAAAAGAUUAACCCAACCGAAUCUACUUCCAAAGCAGAAGAAAAUGAAAAAGUUGAUUCAAAAGUGAAAGCUUUCAAGAAACCAUUGAGUGUAUUUAAAGGCCCCUUACUACACAUCAGCCCAGCAGAAGAACUGUACUUUGGAAGUACAGAAUCCGGAGAGAAGAAAACCUUAAUAGUGUUGACAAAUGUAACUAAAAAUAUAGUGGCAUUUAAGGUGAGAACAACAGCUCCAGAAAAAUACAGAGUCAAGCCAAGCAAUAGCAGCUGUGACCCGGGUGCAUCAGUGGAUAUAGUUGUGUCUCCCCAUGGGGGUUUAACAGUCUCUGCCCAAGACCGUUUUCUGAUAAUGGCUGCAGAAAUGGAACAGUCAUCUGGCACAGGCCCAGCAGAAUUAACUCAGUUUUGGAAAGAAGUUCCCAGAAACAAAGUGAUGGAACAUAGGUUAAGAUGCCAUACUGUUGAAAGCAGUAAACCAAACACUCUUACGUUAAAAGACAAUGCUUUCAAUAUGUCAGAUAAAACCAGUGAAGAUAUAUGUCUACAACUCAGUCGUUUACUAGAAAGCAAUAGGAAGCUUGAAGACCAAGUUCAGCGUUGUAUCUGGUUCCAGCAGCUGCUGCUUUCCUUAACAAUGCUCUUGCUUGCUUUUGUCACCUCUUUCUUCUAUUUAUUGUACAGUUAAAGAAGUGGUGCCGGGUAGGAACCACGGUUCCUUCGUCCAUUAGUUGGAAAAAGUAACAGACCUAAAACUCUACCAAGCUACUAAAAACAUUGCACAUCUGUGCUUCCUAAAAGGAAAUAUGCAGCACGUGGAGGGGAACACAUACAUGUCUUGAAAAUAAACUGCUAGAAUAAAGAAAUGCUGGAGAAAUUGAUUAUAAGAGACUAUAGCUAUUUAGUAAAGUAAGUAAAGGCAUAUCCAUUGUGUAAAUUAAUAGUUUAAAUAUAAUUUAUUUUUUCCUUUUGAUCUGAAUACUUUUAAAGCUUAAGUUUUAUCGUGUAAAUACAUUAGCUAAACUGAAAAGUAUAAGUAACAUGCUUUGUUGCAGCCAAAAAAUGUAAUCUGCUUUUUUAUGACAGAAUUAUUAUAGCUGAGCUGACUUACUAGCUUUUCUAUACUAUGUAUAUAGAAGAACAUGUAUAUUGAGAAAGAAAACAUACUUAUAUAGAGGAAUUUAUGUAACCAUGACUUUGUAAUUUUGAGAAUUCCUCCCAGUGAUGGUCAGUAUUCUUUUGGAAUGUAAACCGAUUUAAUGCCAAACCACCUUAACCUUUGUUUCUCAGUGUUCCUUAACAGCCUGCCUUUUAUUAAUCUCAGGCUUUUUUAUGAACACUCUCAUUUCAGUAGAAUUUGGAAAACUAAGCGUGGUUGGAAUUUCUUUGAAUUCUGUUAGUAAUGCCCAAAAGAAAAGUCUCAAGCAGUCCCCCUAUCCAGUCAUUUUUAUGGAGUUUCAUGUUGUCCACUAUAGCUGGACACUGAACCUUUUGCCUAAUUUAUUAUAAAGGCCUGACCCUCUAUUGUCCCAUCUUCACCCCCAUUCCAGAGCAGAGGAGUCUCUGUGGACCAUGAAUUGCACUGUCUCCCUCCUCAUUUCUAAAUGAAAGGUAUUAGAUAUAAAUUUUUUUGAAAGGUUAGUUGUUUGAGAUGCUAAGCAGGAUAAUAAAUUUAGAUUUUAAAAUGUUCCCUGUAAAAGUCAGCCCAUGACAAGGAAAUUUACAAAAUACUAGAGUAUCUAGAAGGGUGAAAACAAAAAAAAAUAAAAAGAAACACAGACGCCCAGGUGUCAGCUCUCCGUUUAAAGAAUGAAAAAUGUAACUCAUGAUGAUCUGUGAAACCUUCAAACUAGGACCAAUUGACUUACUUGAUAUUCUGCCUUUGAUAUGGUAGUACCCACCCGGUAUUCCUAAAAUCCUAAAAAGAUACACCUUGCAGUAGCAGAGGCAAUGACAUGAGUUUGUUUUCUCAUUAAUAUGACCAGUUUGGGUCUAUGUUGGUUCACAUGUACAUCUACUUUAUAUGAAAGAAAAAACAGUUGUCUGCCUGUAAAAUGUUGAGUUUCGAUUGAGCCAUGUUUGGAGAUUUUAUUACUAUUCUGAAGGGUAGUGUUGUUGGUUUUCAUCUUCAAGAAGUUGAUUCCAAAACUGAGUUAUGAAGAAUGAUAUAACAGUUCCUUCAAAAUUGGCCUAGGAAAUAAAACCUUAAAAGGACACUGGUGUGCUACUUUGUCUUAAUUUGGGCUUUUCUGUUUCAGUUUGCCACCUCCAGCUGUGAAAUGGACUGCAGUCCACCCUAAGUACUGUGCACAGUAUCUCCCUGUGUGUGUGCACAGUGGCUUCCCCUUACAUGGUAGAUUUUUGGCCUUAAUAUAAUCUAAUCCCAAAGUAGUUGUGUAUGUUUUCUGUUCCUUGGCAAAUAAAUGAAGAAAUAAUUAGCCAAGAUUGAAAAUGUAUUGUCCUAACGGUGUCCCUUUAAUGUUUCAUAUGAAAAAUUAUGUUGACCCACUAAAAUAUCCUUGCUCAAUGUCUGGUCAGUUGAAUUUAAUAACAUAUCUUGUUAAUGUUUGUGUGUCUAUUAAAUGUGACUAAGCAGGAUUACUGAAAAUUCACUAUAAAAUCAAAGGCAUCUAAACGUUUGUACUUGUCUUGAUUAAUCAUAUAUUUACACUUGAUUUUUUUCUGUCUUCAUUUGUUUUUAUUUAAUCAUAAUUGCAUGAUUUUUUUGGUACUCUAAUCAGUAAUUUUAUUUUUAAUCAUGUCAUUACCUAUUCAUGACCAAAUUACCAAGGAACCAACAUUUAGAUUUAGAUAUUUGUUUUCACUUAGGAAUGGAAAUUAAUAGAUUUUCCAUGAAAGCAUUAGUGAAAUAUCAUUACCUUGAUCUGCAAGUAGCCUAAAAAUGCGAUUGCUGGUAAACCUGGCCUCAAAUUUCAUACUACCAUAACUGUUUUUAUAUAUUGCCACUAAUUUUGACUGGAUUUAAUAGCACUUUAUUGUACAACUACAAAAAAAAAUAUAUUCCUAGAAUUGUUGCCAGUGUAAUUUCUCUAAUGUUCUGGUGCUUUUCAUAUAUUUUCAGUAUUUUUAUUACUAUAUUGGUAUUUUCUUUGUAUAAAUUGAUUGAUUAAAAGAACAUGUUUUCUAUUUUAAUAUGUUUUAGAAAAAUAAUUACAUUUAUGAAAUAAAUAUCAUCAGGAAAAAAA